CUCUUCGCUUCCCCGUAGCUCCCGCUUUCGCCUCUUCGUUUAUGACUCCGUUGGGCUCCGGCCCUCCUAGAGAGGCCUCCAUAGCGCAGGUUCGUGGGUUCUCGCGGACCUUUUUCCGUGUAGCUUUCUGCUUCUUCCCGGCAUUCCUGUUUCCGUUUUCUCACAGCCCUCUGGCUUUUCCACCACUGAGACACUUUGCGCUCAGGACUUCAGUGACGUCAUCUUUCUGCGGCGCGCGGACACCCGCCGGUGGAAGAAGAAACAGCUCCGCCGUCCUUCGCUUCUUUUGCUGGGCUGCUGCUCCUUCGGCAUCAUGGCGCCGUCGCUGUGGAAGGGGCUGGUGGGCAUCGGUCUCUUUGCCCUAGCCCACGCCGCCUUUUCCGCUGCGCAGCAUCGUUCUUAUAUGCGAUUAACAGAAAAAGAAGAUGAAUCACUGCCAAUAGAUAUAGUUCUUCAGACACUUCUGGCCUUUGCAGUUACCUGUUACGGUAUAGUUCAUAUUGCAGGAGAGUUUAAAGACAUGGAUGCCACUUCAGAACUGAAAAAUAAGACAUUUGAUACGUUAAGGAAUCACCCAUCCUUUUAUGUAUUUAAUCAUCGUGGUCGAGUACUUUUCCGGCCUUCGGAUACAGCAAAUUCUUCAAACCAAGAUGCAUUGUCCUCUAACACAUCAUUGAAGUUACGAAAACUCGAAUCACUGCGUCGUUAAGAUUUUUACAAAUUAUAAUAAUAGGACAGGACACAGAGCUGGAAUAUUGGAGUUUGGGGUAUAAAACACUCCUCCCUGCCCCCAUUAGUAUUUAUAUUGAUCUUUCAGACCUACUUUAGUAAAAAAAACCAUGGCCCUUGUUUAUAUACUGUUAAUCCAAUCAUUAAUGCAGUGUAAGUUAUAUGUGAAAUGAGUCUUUGGUAUUUCAUAUAGGAAUUAUUUUUUUUUUCAUUUAAAACAAAUCCACAUCUUUUGUAAAAGCCACUGUUUUGAACACAUUUCCUUGAAAAAUGUUGGUGGUUUUUGUGAUUAUUUAUUUUUUUAGAUUUCUUUUCUUUUGCACUACAAUUUUUGGAAUCCUUUUGGAAAUACUGUGUGACUGCUGUGUUUUGCAGCAUGAAUUAUAGUAAAAUGGUCUUCAAUUCUUAACAAAUGGACUUCCCUGAUGAGACCAAAAUGGUGAUUUAACAGUUUUUCUUGUGUCCCCUAAAAAGUGGCUCUGCUUCAGAAGUACUUGCCAGUUUUUAAUUUAUUUGUGACUUUUCACCCUACCCUGCUCCCAUAUACCUUCUACCAUCAGCUGUCUUGUUUCAUCAUUUCUCUGAGAUUCUGUGUGCAGUGAGCAAUUUUUGUGUCAGAAAUUCUUUGUCAGAACAAAUAUAUGUAACAGGCUCAACUUACUGUAAAGCUACUUGUGUUCUCUUCAUUUGUCUGUAAAAAUUUCCCUAAUUGAUUAUAUAGUGUAAGAAUAGUUGAAGACUAGUUGAAGACCUUUUGUGAUUUCAUUAUCAUGCCUAUGCAGAAGAAAAAUCAUUGAGGAAAAUUGUCAUUAGCCAGUUUAACUGAUUCAAACUCUGUUUAUUUCAUACUAAACUAGUGAAUAAGUGAAAUAAAGGAAACUCGUCAUUAAUCUAAAGACAGAGUUCAAAGGAAUUGGGCCAAAUAUAUUCUCAGUAUUUGGAACUAAUGUUUUUAAGGUUUUUAGGAAAAUCAGGUCAUUUAAGAAAUUGUUUUGUAGUUUCUGGUUUAUAGCAGUCUUCAAGUUUUCCAUCUUCACUGUAUGUUGCUGAAAGUGAGGAUGAGGAUACAGAGUUGAUAUUUUUAGAAACAGUAAUUUUACUUUUAAGGAAAUUGGCUAGCUCUUUGAGCUAGAGAGCUGUAGGAAGCUCAACAUUUCUUUGUAGAGAACGUUGCUUUUUUUGGAUUGUACAGGUAUAAAAACAUUGCUUUUGUUGAAUUGUAUAGGUGUAAAAAGGGAAUAACUGUAUGCAGGUUUGAAAAGGAAAUGUGCUUUAGGCAUGAGUCAUAAGAUGCCAUUGUACUUGUAGGCAUUUUAUUUUCCUUUAGAAAUGGACAUCAGCUCUUCUCUUCUGACUGGUAACACAUAGCCCCAAAGCAUGAGAUUAUUUUUCAUUGGGUUUUUAUUGUUGUUUAGUUUUGGUUUGUUACGCCAGCCCAGUCUGUCUGCGGAACACUGACUCUGCUCUCUAAUGAGAACAAAGUUAGAAAUCUGCCGAUAACCUAAAAUAAUUUAGAAAUGAAUUAAAAAUGUGAAAUCGGGUUAAAGUGAUGAUGAUAAAAUAGCAUGCAAGAAACAAGCUCCUUCCAUCAGACUUGGCUACUGUUUUCUUCUGGUACGAUUUGGUUUGGAAGAGCCUCUUGUUUCCUUCUCUUUGGGGUAUGUCUUCGUUUCUUAAUAUGUUUGUAACAUUAUUGAGAUAUAAUUCACAUACCUUACAAUUCACUUAUUUUAAGGGUACAAUUUAGUGGUUUUUAGUGUAUUCACAAAGUUGUGUAACCGUGACCACAGUCAAUUUUAGAACAUUUCGUUACCCCAAAAAGAAACCCUGUACCCUUGAGCAGUCACCUCUCAUUUUCUCCCAGUGCCCACCCCAUCCCCGAGCCCCUGGCAACCACUAAUCUAUUUCUCUCUCUGUAGAUUUGCUUAUUCUGGUCAUUUCAUAUAAAUGGAAUUCUACAAUAUUCGGUCUUUUGGGACUGGCUUCCCAAAUAUGAUUUUCUAUAUGGAGUGAGAAAAUUCUUCUCAUCUUGAGAACUCUUAUUGCUGUGAAAGGGAGUGGUUGGUAAAAUCAAUAGAUUUCAGGCAAGAGGGCCAGAUACCUAACAGGUUUUUCUCCGUGAAUCUUAUGCUGAGUAGUUUUUCCUCAUAACCAAGCAUUUAUGAUAUAUUACUACUUAUAAUACUGUGGCUAGUCUCUAGAAUGGAUGUUGAAAUCUUUGCCUCCUCAGUCGGGAAGAGUCCUGCUAAAAAUCAGGCUAAAAAUCAGGCCAAAAAUCAGGCCAAAUGACUUGGCAAAUAAUUGACAAAGUGGUUUUCACGUGUGUCUAUCUUUGCUAGCAGCUUGUAUACCUCAGGCCAGGUGAGCUCCCCAAAUUUCUUUUUUCAUUUACUCCAGUGAGUUUCUGCUGUCUUUUUCAAGUAUGUACCAUAGGACUUAAAGGUGAUUUGGAUGCGUUGUAACACUGCUAAAUAUGCUAAGUACAGAAUUUUAUCUACAGUACUGUGAGACAGUCAAUUAUUGCCUAGGGUAGUUCAAAAAUAUGAUGUGAGCUAGUUAAGCCUUUGCUUGACUGAUUUCAGUGAUAUUCAGAAGUGUGUACCAAUCAAGGCUCUUUAAAAUACGGAACGACUCACUUAAUAACCAGGGAACCAGCCAAAUACUGUGCAGCCGCAGAAUAUGCAUAUCAAUGAGUUGGAGGUGAUUAUUCUCUGUAACUCCCUAAUGAUUGUUUUCUAAGCAUUGUGGCUUCUCAGUGGCUUGACAGCAUCUUCCUGGUUGUAUGUGGCCUGUUUACAUGAUGUAUUGAAUAAUGUUGUUUGUUGUGAGCAUCAAUGCCUGUAACACCAAACUAAACACGUGUUUUUGGGAUAUGUUUCCAAUCUUUAAAUGACCUUGCCCUGUCCAAUAAAUAAAUGAUUGUCUCACCCUGUUUUUGGUAGUGUUUUUUGGGCUUUUUUUUUUUGGACUUUUAAUCUCAUUUCUUCUGCUUUUCUGUCCCCAGAAAAAUGUAAGAGCUAAUUUUAUGACUGUAUUUUUCUACUGUGAUGCUGUUUUACUGAAUUCAAUGGAUAAUUUAAUUGUACAUGUAAAAUCUUACUGCAGUUUUAUGUUUUUAAUAGUCAAAAUAGAAUGUAUAAUCUUGAUGAUGUUUAUAAAUCAUCAAAUGCCCUUUGGGGUGUAAAAAUGGGUUCUUGAGCAGCAGUGUCUAAUGAUUCCAUCACAAAUUUGUUAUAAAGCCAAACUCCCAUUGAAAGUGUCACUUUAUACUUAAUAGGAAAUCGUUAUGAUUAAAGCAUCAAGGAAGCAAAUAUAAAGUUUAAUGAAAAUCCAAGGGGAAGUUCUAAAUUGCAAAACUUGGCACUUAUCUACAGUAUUUUGAAAAAUAACACCACCGGUAUUCAAACCUACCUAGGAAUAUCUCAAAAUAACCUGUUAAUUAAGUGUUCUUAGAAAGGGGAGUGGGGGCAAGAAAGAUGAUGUAUGCACAUGGCGAAAAGAUCAGAUGGUACAGAAAGGUAUAAAAACUUGGUCCCUUCCCUCCUACCCUAAUACUCCUCUCCAAAAGUAACCAGUUUCAAGUGUCUUGUACUCACAGGAAAACAAUUUUUUAUUUUUUAUCAGCAAAUUUGUACUUUAAAAAUUUCACAUUAAUAGAAUCAGACUAUAUAUACUCUUCUGUACCUUGCUUUUUUUGCUACCUGUGUUUUAUGAGAUCUUUCUGUAUCAGUAUAUAUAAAAAUACCUCAUUAUUUUUAGCGGCUGUGUGGUAUUCUAAUGUUUGAAUGUGUUACAAAUGUUCAAACACUGAUAGGCUCUUUAGGUUGUUUCCAAUAUUAAAUCACAUUGUGGUGAAUAUACUUGUACAUAUAAUGAGUUUUUAUUCUACAGUGUACCUAGCAAUACAAUUGCUGGAUCAGAGGGUAUUUUUUAUUUUCAGUUCAGUAGUUACUGCCAAAUUGUCCUCUAGAAAUCUUUGCCCAGUAUGCUUCCACAUAUAAUGUAUGAGAAUGAUUAUUUACCAAACCCAUGCCAAUACUGGGUACUAAACUUUUGAAGUCUGAUCAUGUGAAAGUGAAUAAAUGGUAUCUUGCGUUUUAAUGAAGUUCUAAUGCAUUUUAAUGAAGGUCUGGUACAUUUUAAUGAAGGAGAUGGAACACAUUUUCAUGUUUAUUGAUUACUGAUAUUUCCUGUGAAAUGUGUAGUCAUGUUCUGUUUUCUAUUAGGUGGUAUGUGUUUUAUUGAUUUGUAUGAGCUUUUUGUAAGCUAAGAAAAUUGGUCCAUUGUCAUGUUUAAUAAUAUUUUCCUAAGUUUUAUUUAUGUAGUUAAACUUAGUCUUUACAGCUUCUGAGAUUUUGCCUUGCUUAGAAAGGCCACCUUUGCAUUUAAGAAUAAAUUUAAUGUAUUUUUCCAGUA